ACUCCAUGGUAACGACGCUCGGCCCGAAGAUGGCGGCCGAAUGGGGCGGAGGAGUGGGUUACUCGGGCUCAGGCCCGGGCCGGAGCCGGUGGCGCUGGAGCGGGUCUGUGUGGGUCCGAAGCGUUUUACUCCUGUUGGGCGGGCUCCGGGCCAGCGCCACAUCUACUCCCGUCUCCUUGGGCAGUUCCCCUCCCUGCCGGCACCACGUCCCCUCUGACACUGAGGUCAUAAAUAAAGUUCAUCUUAAGGCAAAUCAUGUGGUCAAGAGAGAUGUUGAUGAGCAUUUAAGAAUCAAGACUGUCUAUGAUAAAAGUGUUGAAGAGUUGCUCCCUGAGAAAAAGAAUCUUGUAAAGAACAAGCUUUUCCCACAAGCGAUUUCUUAUUUAGAGAAGACUUUUCAGGUCCGUCGACCUGCGGGCACUAUCUUACUUAGCAGACAAUGUGCAACAAACCAAUACCUCCGGAAGGAAAACGAUCCUCACAGGUACUGCACCGGGGAGUGUGCCGCACACACAAAGUGCGGCCCCGUUAUUGUUCCUGAGGAACAUCUCCAGCAAUGCCGGGUCUACCGUGGGGGUAAGUGGCCUCAUGGAGCAGUGGGUGUGCCAGACCAAGAAGGCAUCUCAGAUGCAGACUUUGUUCUUUACGUUGGUGCUCUGGCCACCGAGAGAUGCAGCCAUGAAAACAUCAUCUCUUAUGCAGCCUAUUGUCAGCAGGAAGCAAACAUGGACAGGCCAAUAGCAGGAUAUGCUAACCUGUGUCCAAAUAUGAUCUCUACCCAGCCUCAGGAGUUUGUUGGGAUGCUGUCCACAGUGAAACAUGAGGUUAUUCAUGCCCUGGGUUUCUCUGCUGGGCUGUUUGCAUUCUACCAUGAUAAAGAUGGAAAUCCUCUCACUUCAAGAUUUGCAGAUGGCCUCCCACCUUUUAAUUAUAGUCUGGGAUUAUAUCAAUGGAGUGAUAAAGUAGUUCGAAAAGUGGAGAGAUUAUGGGAUGUUCGAGAUAAUAAGAUAGUUCGUCACACUGUGUAUCUCCUGGUAACGCCUCGUGUUGUUGAGGAAGCACGAAAACAUUUUGAUUGUCCAGUUCUAGAGGGAAUGGAACUUGAAAAUCAAGGUGGUGUGGGCACUGAGCUCAACCAUUGGGAAAAAAGGUUAUUAGAGAAUGAAGCGAUGACUGGUUCUCACACUCAGAAUCGAGUACUCUCUCGAAUCACUCUGGCAUUAAUGGAGGACACUGGCUGGUAUAAAGCAAAUUACAGCAUGGCUGAGAAGUUAGACUGGGGCCGAGGAAUGGGCUGUGACUUUGUCAGGAAGAGCUGUAAAUUCUGGAUUGAUCAGCAGAGACAAAAGAGACAGAUGCUGAGCCCUUACUGUGACACGCUCAGAAGUAACCCACUGCAGCUAACUUGCAGACAGGACCAGAGAGCAGUUGCCGUGUGUAAUUUGCAGAAGUUCCCUAAGCCUUUACCACAGGAAUACCAGUACUUUGAUGAACUCAGUGGAAUACCUGCAGAAGAUUUGCCUUAUUAUGGUGGCUCCGUGGAAAUUGCUGACUACUGCCCUUUCAGUCAGGAAUUCAGUUGGCAUUUAAGUGGUGAAUAUCAGCGCAGCUCAGAUUGUAGAAUAUUGGAAAAUCAACCAGAAAUUUUUAAGAACUAUGGCGCUGAAAAGUAUGGACCUCAUUCCGUUUGUCUAAUUCAGAAAUCAGCAUUCGUUAUGGAGAAGUGUGAGAGGAAGCUGAGUUACCCAGACUGGGGAAGCGGAUGCUAUCAGGUUUCUUGUUCUCCUCAAGGUCUGAAAGUUUGGGUCCAAGAUACUUCAUAUUUGUGUAGUCGGGCUGGGCAGGUCCUCCCUGUCAGUAUCCAGAUGAAUGGCUGGAUUCACGAUGGAAACCUGCUCUGCCCAUCAUGUUGGGACUUCUGUGAGCUCUGUCCUCCAGAAACAGAUCCUCCAGCCACUAACCUGACCCGAGCUCUGCCACUUGAUCUUUGUUCCUGUUCCUCGAGCCUGGUGGUCACCCUCUGGCUUCUGCUAGGCAAUCUGUUUCCUCUGCUGGCUGGAUUUCUUCUGUGUAUAUGGCACUAGGAAUGGAAAAGUGGAUCUUCAAGAUAUUCUUUUAUGUUAUGUUCUUGUGAACAAAGCACAAAGUUUGAGUGAGUGCCAACCUAUGCAGAUGGUAGAAGUGGCAUUCCUGGCUUUGGCUUGGAAGAAUUGACGACCAUCAGACCUUGAAGCAGAACUUCACAGCAGCCUGUCCUCAUCAGCAACCCAACCACCUUCAUCAGCAACCCAACCACCUUCAUCAGCAACCCAACCACCUCGUCAGCAACCCAACCACCUCGUCAGCAACCCAACCACCUCGUCAGCAACCCAGCCACCUUCAUCAGCAACCCAACCACCUCAUCAGCAACCCAGCCACCUUCAUCAGCAACCCAACCACCUCAUCAGCAAACCAACCACUUUCAUCUGCAACCCAACCACUUUCAUCAGCAACUCAACACCUUCAUCUGCAACCCAACCACCUUCAUCAGCAAACCAACCACCUUCUUCAGCAACCCAACCACCUCAUCUUGGAGAAGGAGAAGGAACUGCAAGCCACCAAGUCUUCAUUUUUCAGGGUUUGUAAUCUUCCCAAAGUUUUCCUUUGAAAAUAGGAUAAUGGGUGGAAUUUUCAGAGUGAUUACAUACCUCAACAUUUUUAUUAACAUACAACAAUGGGAAAGUUCAUCAUCCAUAUACUGCAGUCACUUAAACAACAGCCAAUUAUUGCAAGAUUAGAAUUGGAGAUCUUGUCCUCAAAAGUAUAAAUUGUCCUUUGAGUUAUAGAAAAUAAUGGAAUUGGGAUUUCUACAUAUCAUUAUUAUACCUAUUUUAAAUUUAAUGGCAGCCAGGCAUGGUUCCAGCUACUUGGGAGGCUGAGGCAGGAGGAUCGCUUGAGCCCAGGAGUUCAAGGCUGCAGUGAGCUAUGAUUGCACCACUGUAUUCCAGCCUGCACGAUAGAGUUAGACCCUGUAUCUUAAAAAAAAAAAAAUUAAUGGCUGGUAUAUAGUAAACUUAAUUCACUGUUCCCAUUGUUCUAAAGAAUUUUUUUAAAUAAUGUUUCAUUAAAUCUUAUGAUUUAACCGUGCUUGCCCUUUUUGCCAGCUAUGUGGCAGUUUACGGCAGAACUGCUGUCAGUGUGCUGGUAGCCCUCUAUUCAUCCCUCCUCAGAGCCCAGCUUCCAGAACUGCUAUCACUGUGCUGGUAGCCCUCUGUAUUCAUCCCUCUUCAGAGCUCAGCUUCUGGUUGUAUUCUCCAUGAGUUUAAUAAUGACAUGAAAAAAUGUGGAAGCCGAGAGAGUAAAAUACUCUGCCCUGUAAAAACAUGGAAGACAUGCAAACAGAAAAAAAAUAAUUGUAUUGUUUUAGAUAAUACUUAAGACAACUGUGAAACAACAAAAACACAACUAUUCCUUUGUGACCGAUGAAGAUAAAAAGAAAUUCUGGUAAAGACGGGUAUGCAGUUUUUUAAAAUGGGUUAAGAAAUUGUUGCAGAAGAAUUUCUAACAUCUGAAAAUGGUUUUAUGUUUAAGAAGGAUGGUCUGAAUUGUGUACUAAUAGCAAGGUAUAAGUUUGGUGUAGAGCCUAUCCAGUAGCGUCCACUGUACCACUUUUAAGUAAGACUCAGUCCACAGAAGCUGGAAGAUUGCCUUCGCUUUAAAUAUCCUUUACCUUCUGCAUUUGACACUCCUCCUGUUACUACAUAGAUUCCGGUCCCCAGAAGCAAUUUUACACUGGUACUAGAGCUUACCAGCCCCAUUUAGUAAUUUUUAAUGGCUAGAUGAGGUUUAACAAGAAUAUGAAAAGAAAAAAGAAAAAAUAUAUUCAUGAAUGAUAGGCGAUGCCCAUUCUUUCUCUCAAGCUAAUGAAGUCCUAUGGCAUUCUAACCACAACCCUCGGACAGACUCCUCCUAUUCCUCCAUGGCAUUGUAACCACAACCCUCGGACAGACUCCUCCUAUUCCUCCAUGGCAUUGUAACCACAACCCUCGGACAGACUCCUCCUACUCCUCCAUGGCAUUGUAACCACAACCCUCGGACAGACUCCUCCUACUCCUCCAUGGCAUUGUAACCACAACCCUCGGACAGACUCCUCCUACUCCUCCAUGGCAUUGUAACCACAACCCUCGGACAGACUCCUCCUAUUCCUCCAUGGCAUUGUAACCACAACCCUCGGACAGACUCCUCCUAUUCCUCCAUGGCAUUGUAACCACAACCCUCGGACAGACUCCUCCUAUUCCUCCAUGGCAUUGUAACCACAACCCUCGGACAGACUCCUAUUCCUCCAUGGCAUUGUAACCACAACCCUCGGACAGACUCCUCCUAUUCCUCCAUGGCAUUGUAACCACAACCCUCGGACAGACUCCUUCUGUUCCUCCUUUCCUCGUCCUUCCCUGCUUUUCGUCCAUUCAGCAUAUAGCUAUUCAGUACUCCAUUGAAGAAAUUAUGCUAAGUGAGCAAAGCAACAUAAUUACUAAGAAUUAAUUCUGAUUAUUUGGCACUAGAGCCAACAGCAACCCCAGCACAGAGGAAAGUCGCUUUUUUUUCAAAUGCAUAAAUUUAAAGUAUGUAUUUGCAUGCAGUUUUAAAUGGGAGGUAUUUGUCAUUGUGAAAAGCUGGGAAUCUCAAACAUAGUCAACUUAACUAAAAAGAAGCUAAUACAGGUUGAGCAUUCCUAAUCCAAAAAUCCAGAAUCCAAAUUGCUCCAAAAUCUGAAACUUUCUGAAUGCUGACCUGAUACUACAAGUAGAAAAUUCCACAUACAAGUACUUAACACAAACUUUGUUUCAUGCACAAACUACUAAAAAUAUUGUAUAAAAUUACCUUCAGGCAGUGUGUGUAGUUAUAUAUGAAACAUGAAUUUCAUGUUUAGACUUGGGUCCAUGCCCAAGAUACCUCAUUAGGUAUCUGUAAAUAUCCGAAAUCCAAAAAAAAGUCUGAAAUCUGAAACACUUCUGGUCCCAAGCAUUUCAGUAAGUGAUGCUCAACCUGCGUAAUGGUCUGCGGGCCAGUGCUCAUUUUCUGCCUAUGUUGUACAUACUUUAAAUUGUGUAAAUUAAAAGUCAAAGCAAAGAGUCUAUUUUUAAAGAAACUUACAAUAAUCUAAACAUAUACUUCUUAUGAUUAUGAAUCAUCCUGCAAAGCUGAAUGAAGAAUUUUACCAAAAAUACAAUGAAUUAAUCAUAUAUUUGAGAGUCACAGUGAUAGGUUCGACUAUAUUUUGACUGUUGUGUAGUGGCACCGUUUAGGUAGUAUUGUUUCUGAGCAUGGUGCUUUUUAUACUUGAAAUAUAUUUUUGCUUUAUUUUUUAUUGAUAUAAUUAUAUUUGCACUAAUGGCUUUCUGAAGAAAAUAUUAUAGAUGACAUUUUUUGUAUAUAUAUUUAUUAAGCUUGGGAACCUGGUCGCCCAGUGUUUUCUCUGGACAAAUGUGAAACUGGAUAAAGUAUGGAUAAAGUCUUGAGUUCCUCAGGGUAACUGUGUUGAUGUCUCCCGUCCUCUUCAGUAAGGCUUGAAUAUGAUUUUACUCAUCAUUGAUUCUGCAUAGUGUACCCAGCAAGACUUAGAAGGACACUGAACCUGUCAGAGAUUUUAAGAGGCACAUUUUAGUCACUUUGAAUAUGGUAGUGGUGGGCGCGGUGACUGAAGCCUGUAAUCUCAGCACUUCGGGAGGCCAAGGCAAGCAGAUCACGAGAUCAGGAGUUUGAGGUUACAGUGAGCUGAUCGCACCACUGCACUGCAGCCUGGAUGACAGAGUGAGACUUUCUUGGGAAAAAAAAAAAUGACAGUGAAGCAGACUUUUAGAAUCCGAGAUGUCAUUGCAGAAUUAUUGGUAUAAAAUUCAGCUGCAAAGUGAAGAAAUUGAAAUGGCCCACACGUUGAUAUCCUGUGGCAGGUUAUACCCUUCAUGUUAGCAAAGACGAAGCCACGUCGCUGUGUUAAGAGGGACAGGCUGGGCCGGCUGCAGCUGUAGUGGAAGUGAGGGACACAGGGAAGGAAUGGGGAGCAGCAAUUUGGGGACAGUAGACUGGAGUCACUUUCUGACUCAAAAAGGGUCAAGUACUUAUUAAAAACUAUCUUGGUUUUCUGUUCAGACUUAGGCUCAUUUUGAUCAUUUUAAGGUCCCAGUUGUCAAAAAUAUCAAGUGAAUUUGUCUCAGGUUUUCAGAAACAAAAUUUACAGGAAGGAAGCAAAAGCCAUGUCAGUAGCCUUGAGCUGACAGCUUUAAAGAAACUGGCAAACAGGUAGGUUGUCCUCAUAUAGAUCCUUCCAGUAUUCUGAAAAACAUCCUUUUAUUUCUUAAAACCAGUAACCCUUACAUUUUUCCUAUAGGAUAGUUAUUUUUGUUGAGAUCAAAUAGACAUUCUAUAAAUGUUAUAAAUUAUGCUUGCAGUUACUCAGCCUAUCUAGGCUUAAGGUUUAUCAAUAUUUGAAGUUGAAACAUCAUCUUAUGAGGUUUAGUUUUAGGAAGAUAAAUAAAUAUAUCAAAGUAUUUCAUAAAGUUGUAUCAAUGUUCCUUCUAACAUUAGAAGACUUACUGACUGAGGCCAUCUGUGAACGACUAGGUGAUCUCAGAAUCCUUCCAGCUCUAAUACCCUCUGACUAACACUCACCCAGAAUUGCUGUCUGUGCUGGCUGUGAUCUGCCUCCAGGAGCAUACGCCAUCCUGCGUGCUGUGUCCAUCACAGUGUCUGUGCUCGGUGCCUUACCACUGUCCGUGUCCUUGGACGCUGACUGGACAGAGAGGAGCCUGUCUCUCAGGGCACAUGAGUCGUCGUGGCAGGAGGAGACGGGCCUCAGUCACAGUGUCACAGACCCUUGUCACAGUGGACACUAGUCAUUCCUGCCAUGUCCUUGCAGCCCAGGAGGACUAAAAAGAUUUUAAUGAAGUCUGUGUUACUCAUUCUGAAGAAAAGAACUUACCUGAGAGGAGUAAUAUUUUUUUAAUAUAUAUUGGGUCAGGGACAGGGAUGGAGUGGUUGUUUUAUGUUUACAUUUUUAAUAAGUAAAAUAGAAGAUUUAAGAACUAAUAUUUAUGGUAUUGAACUUUAAGUGUGAUAUAUUCCUUAGAAAAACACAACUUUAAUAAAAAUGGAAACUAA